GCGUUUUGCCACAGAGCCGUAAAGGCGCGCGGGAACAUGGGGCUGUAUGCUGCAGCUGCAGGCGUGUUGGCCGGCGUGGAGAGCCGCCAGGGCUCUAUCAAGGGGUUGGUGUACUCCAGCAACUUCCAGAACGUGAAGCAGCUGUACGCGCUGGUGUGCGAAACGCAGCGCUACUCCGCCGUGCUGGAUGCUGUGAUCGCCAGCGCCGGCCUCCUCCGUGCGGAGAAGAAGCUGCGGCCGCACCUGGCCAAGGUGCUAGUGUAUGAGUUGUUGUUGGGAAAGGGCUUUCGAGGGGGUGGGGGCCGAUGGAAGGCUCUGUUGGGCCGGCACCAGGCGAGGCUCAAGGCUGAGUUGGCUCGGCUCAAGGUUCAUCGGGGUGUGAGCCGGAAUGAGGACCUGUUGGAAGUGGGAUCCAGGCCUGGUCCAGCCUCCCAGCUGCCUCGAUUUGUGCGUGUGAACACUCUCAAGACCUGCUCCGAUGAUGUAGUUGAUUAUUUCAAGAGACAAGGUUUCUCCUAUCAGGGUCGGGCUUCCAGCCUCGAUGACUUACGAGCCCUCAAGGGGAAGCAUUUUCUCCUGGACCCCUUGAUGCCGGAGCUGCUGGUGUUUCCCGCCCAGACAGAUCUGCAUGAACACCCACUGUACCGGGCCGGACACCUCAUUCUGCAGGACAGGGCCAGCUGUCUCCCAGCCAUGCUGCUGGACCCCCCGCCAGGCUCCCAUGUCAUCGAUGCCUGUGCCGCCCCAGGCAAUAAGACCAGUCACUUGGCUGCUCUUCUGAAGAACCAAGGGAAGAUCUUUGCCUUUGACCUGGAUGCCAAGCGGCUGGCAUCCAUGGCCACGCUGCUGGCCCGGGCUGGCGUCUCUUGCUGUGAACUGGCUGAGGAGGACUUCCUGGCGGUCUCCCCCUCGGAUCCACGCUACCAUGAGGUCCACUACAUCCUGCUGGAUCCUUCCUGCAGUGGCUCGGGUAUGCCGAGCAGACAGCUGGAGGAGCCCGGGGCAGGCACACCUAGCCCGGUGCGUCUGCAUGCCCUGGCAGGGUUCCAGCAGCGAGCCCUGUGCCACGCACUCACUUUCCCUUCCCUGCAGCGGCUCGUCUACUCCACGUGCUCCCUCUGCCAGGAGGAGAAUGAAGACGUGGUGCGAGAUGCGCUGCAGCAGAACCCGGGCGCCUUCAGGCUAGCUCCCGCCCUGCCUGCCUGGCCCCACCGAGGCCUGAGCACGUUCCCGGGUGCCGAGCACUGCCUCCGGGCCUCCCCUGAGACCACACUCAGCAGUGGCUUCUUCGUUGCUGUAAUUGAACGGGUCGAGGUGCCAAGGUGAGUGAGUGGGGGCGUGCUUGGGAGGCGCAGGAUGGCACCGGCACAUCUAACAUCUACACUUCUCUAGCUCAGCCUCACAGGCCAAAGCAUCAGCACCAGAACGCACACCCAGCCCAGCCCCAAAGAGAAAGAAGAGACAGCAAAGAGCCGCAGCCGGUGCUUGCACACCGCCUUGCACAUAGCAGAGGCUCCGGGCUGACUCCUUCCUGGUGGGAAAGGAAGAUGCCUGUCCUCUCCGUGGAGGACCCUGGGCCCUCACCGCAGGAAGCAGUUUGGGUUUUGAAAGGUUAUUGGGUCCCUUCCUUGGGCUGUGUUCUUGCUGGUGAGCAAAGUGUUGCCUGCAAAAAUAAAAUGCAGAACGUACUCUACGAUAGAUCACAGUUUUUUAUUCUUAAUGUCACAAGCAGGAGAAAAAUCUCACAUUCAUACUAAAAGUUCCAACUAGACUCAACAGGAAUGAAGUCUCUAUUUGUAAUGGAAAGUCCCAGCCUCCCGCUGCCGUCCAGUGCGUGUACUGUACACAUCCACACUCACACUCACUCAGGGUUCCCGGACCGGCUGUCCUGCCUGCGGAACUGAGGUAAACUAGCUCAGGUGCUGACACUAGGAGGGUCUACCUUACAUAAGGUACAGGUAGAAGCUUGAUUGCUAGGCCCAGGCCCACCCAGACCCUCCAAUCCUAACAGGUAUUUAGGCUUGAGGUUCACUCCCUCCUCAGCUGCACACGCAGCCAGGUAUUAACGAGGAUCAGAGCUGUUCUGAGGGGUGGGAAGGAGCAGCCCCACCACCACUCACUCACCCUCAGUCACAUCGGGGAGGGGGCACCAGUUACAUUUACAUCACAUUAUUUAUAAAAUAAGAAUUACAUUUCAUAUAACAUGGCCAGAAGGAGCUCUAGUCCCCCAGGAAAGCUGCCGGGGACAGCAUUUGAGCCUCUUCUUUGCACAGGCAUAACUUAACUAUACAGCUAAUUCCUAGUUAAUAGCAUUUAUACUUAACCACCUCAAUGAACCAAGCUUGAAGGAAUUUAAAAGGCAAUUUAGCUUAAAUACAAAAAUAAAUUUUUGUUAAAAAACGUUUA